AAGUUAUUAAAGAUGGCGACGGAGCGCAGUCGCUCCGCGAUGGACUCGCCGGUCCCGGCCUCUAUGUUCGCCCCCGAGCCCAGCUCCCCGGGGGCGGCCAGGGCCGCGGCGGCCGCCGCCCGACUCCACGGCGGCUUUGACUCGGACUGCAGCGAGGACGGCGAGGCGCUCAACGGCGAGCCAGAGCUGGACCUCACCAGCAAGCUGGUUCUAGUGAGCCCUACAUCAGAGCAGUAUGACAGCCUACUUCGGCAGAUGUGGGAGAGGAUGGACGAGGGAUGCGGAGAGACCAUAUAUGUCAUUGGGCAGGGAUCAGAUGGGACUGAGUAUGGGCUGAGUGAAGCUGACAUGGAGGCCUCCUACGCCACAGUGAAGAGCAUGGCGGAACAGAUAGAGGCCGAUGUCAUCCUUCUGCGGGAACGGCAAGAAGCUGGGGGCCGCGUGCGUGAUUACCUGGUCCGGAAACGAGUAGGAGACAAUGACUUCCUGGAGGUCAGAUGUAUGGGUUCAUCUACACGCAGGGUAGCAGUGGUGGGCAACGUGGAUGCUGGCAAAAGCACGCUUCUGGGGGUCCUGACACAUGGGGAGCUGGACAAUGGCCGAGGCUUUGCCCGCCAGAAACUCUUCCGCCACAAACAUGAAAUUGAAUCUGGUCGCACCAGCAGUGUGGGCAACGACAUUCUGGGCUUUGACAGUGAAGGCAAUGUAGUGAACAAGCCUGACAGCCACGGCGGCAGCCUGGAGUGGACCAAGAUCUGUGAGAAGUCCACGAAAGUCAUUACCUUCAUCGACUUGGCUGGUCAUGAGAAGUACCUGAAAACCACUGUCUUCGGCAUGACAGGCCAUCUGCCUGACUUCUGCAUGCUCAUGGUGGGCAGCAAUGCUGGCAUCGUGGGGAUGACCAAAGAACACCUGGGCUUGGCACUGGCACUCAAUGUACCUGUCUUUGUGGUAGUCACCAAGAUUGACAUGUGUCCUGCCAACAUCCUGCAAGAAACCCUGAAGCUGUUACAGCGCCUGCUGAAGUCACCAGGCUGCCGGAAGAUCCCCGUGCUGGUGCAGAGCAAAGAUGAUGUGAUUGUCACAGCCUCCAACUUCAGCUCUGAAAGGAUGUGCCCGAUAUUCCAGAUCUCCAACGUUACAGGCGAGAACCUAGAUCUGCUGAAGAUGUUCCUCAACCUCCUCUCCCCCCGCACCAGCUACAGGGAGGAGGAGCCUGCUGAGUUUCAGAUUGAUGACACCUACUCCGUCCCGGGUGUGGGGACAGUGGUUUCGGGGACAACACUGAGAGGCCUGAUCAAGCUGAAUGACACGCUGCUGCUGGGCCCAGACCCCUUGGGUAACUUCCUGUCCAUUGCUGUCAAAUCCAUCCAUCGCAAGCGCAUGCCUGUCAAGGAGGUGCGGGGUGGCCAGACAGCAUCCUUUGCGCUGAAGAAGAUCAAGCGCUCGUCCAUCCGGAAGGGCAUGGUGAUGGUUUCCCCACGUUUGAAUCCCCAAGCCUCCUGGGAGUUUGAGGCCGAGAUUCUCGUCCUCCACCACCCCACCACAAUUAGCCCGCGCUACCAGGCCAUGGUGCACUGUGGGAGCAUCAGGCAGACAGCCACCAUUCUGAGCAUGGACAAGGACUGUCUGCGCACUGGGGACAAGGCCACUGUACACUUCCGCUUCAUCAAGACCCCUGAGUACCUGCACAUAGACCAGCGGCUGGUGUUCCGGGAAGGCCGCACCAAGGCUGUCGGCACCAUCACCAAGCUCCUCCAGACCACCAACAACUCCCCAAUGAACUCCAAGCCGCAGCAGAUUAAAAUGCAGUCGACGAAAAAGGGCCCCCUGACGAAACGAGACGAGGGGGGCCCGUCUGGUGGGCCAGCAGUAGGAGCACCCCCACCUGGAGAUGAAGCCUCCUCUGUAGGGGCAGGGCAACCAGCUGCGUCCAGCAAUCUCCAGCCUCAGCCUAAGCCCAGCAGUGGAGGCCGGCGACGAGGGGGCCAGCGCCACAAGUCACAGGUCCAAGGGGCAAAUAGCGAAUUCCCAUGGAGGAGAAUCACUGCACUCCAAGUGGACGUGGCUGGUAGGAAGCUUCCCUCAUGCUGCCCUUCUGGAAGGUGCCUUCCCCUGUGCUGACGUCUGCAGGAUGCGUGUUACACCCCAUUUGGAUAUCACAUCUUGAGCUGUGGGAAAGGAGAGCAGGGCUUCCCUCUCUGAACCCCAUGCCUGGCAGGGUAAGUGCCCAGGGAGCACCUGCUGCCUGGAUGGGGAGUCUGCGCCACUUCUGCUAGCACAGCAGCAUCCCGUACCUGAAAGUGAAACGUCUGAAUAGGCUCGCCGUCCUGAUCGUAAGUGAACUUGCCAAGGAGUGUCCCCUCCUGCUGCAGGUCUUCGUCAAACCCCUGCAAAGAGAGCGGAGGGAAGUGGGGAGGGGCUGGAGCAGGGAGAACACCCCUCCCCACUCCAAUCCCUGCUCCUCCCACCCAGCAGGUCAGGCACCAGAGUGGCCUAUGACAAGUCACUUCACUCUCUUGUGCCACAGUUUCUGCCUCCAAAGCCUAAGGUAACAGGGACUGAAGUGCUGUCUCCCACCCUAGCUCCUCCUCUUCCAAAUCCACUCCCCUCCCUUCCAGUCCAAGGGUGACCCUGACUUGAUCCUCAGUAGAGAGGCCCACAGGAUCCCCCUGCAGCCCCUCUGGCCCCACCACAGGACAGAUACUCACAAAGAUGGCGAAGUCCUUGGGGGCACUGGAGAUAGUGCUGUUGGGUGACAAGGCCUUGGGCACAUGCUCUAAGGUAACGGCUGUGGGGCGGAUGCGGGCAGAGAGGCGGACCACGGCGAAGCCUUGUGGCCCCUGGAAGGCCCAGCAGUUGCCUGGGUGCACAUCUGGCUGGAGGAGCAGAAAGUCAUGUCAGGACAGGGCCCUGAGUCCAGCUCUUGCUGACCCCAGAUGGGACCAGCCCUCAGUGUGCUCAGAGCCCCCGCUGCUGUGCUUGCCAGGUGCCCACCUGGAGGAUGACUCGGGGUGACUGGGAGUGGUACCACAGGGGGAUGCCGAAGAGGCUGAGGAGGGCCGUCUUGGUCUCGUAGGUCUCAGAACAUCGGGUGCUGAUGACGCUGGCCCCUGAGACAGGAGAGGAAGGCAGGGUGGGCUCCCGCACGGGAGGAGGGCCCCGCUCAGGCCAUUGGCUGUCUCCUCGCUGAAGGUGGACGGCAGAUGCCCCAGGCCUAGCCUUUAACCCUAACCGAGAUGCUCAGAGCAGCUUUAAAGGUCAGCCUCUCCCUGGCCCAGGAUGGUACUCGGUACGUCCUGACUUCCCUGAAUUGCCACUUGCCUUUGUCAUGGGUACUAGGUUGGGUGAUUUCUGCUGAUCCUGAGCUUUGCUUGCUCUGCCCCACCACCAACCUGGUAGAUGCCAGGGGACCGGCCAUUGCGGGGUCCAGGACAAGGCAGAGCGAGGAAAGCAGAGCACGUACCUCCUGACUCCAGGGCGUAGUCUGCCAGCCCGAUGCGGUCCUCACUGUAGCGCUGCAGGGCCUGCUUCACGAUGUGGUGCACCUGCUGCAAUGCAGGCACCAGGAGACGGUUGCAGCAGGGAGCAGACGUGUCCCCCUGUCACCUCGUGGCCGUGGGCCAAGGACCCAUGGGCUGACCCCUUCUAGGCUUGCACUGUGCUGGUGCCCAGGCAGAUGUGGGCACACUGCCACCCACCCAUGCCAGCCCCACAGCAUGCAAAGCCUCCUGCUUGGCACUUCCAUCCUGGAACCUGCCAGGGAGCUGGCAGUGUGGGACUGUCCAGGGCUCCCAGGGAGGAGAGCUGUGGGUGGGUGUGUGGAGAGGGGCAUGUGGGCCUCACCUCCUCUGUCACUCCAAUCACACCUUCUUUCUGCAGCGUCAGGCUCAGGGAGGCCGCGGCUUCCCUGGCCGACUUGCCCUGCAUCUCUGCCACAUGGGUGAGGAUCUUGCUCUCCAGCUCUCGCAGCUGAGCUUGCAUCUCCUCUCUCUGAAGGAGCCCCACGCGGCCCCCUCCACCUCGGGCAAGGAACUGACUGAUCCAGGCCGGGAACUGAGAUUCCACCUAUAGGAACCCAAAGGGGUGUCACCCUGGGGGGCUUGCAGGGACAGCAGGAGCUGCUAUGACAGGGCUAGUGCUUAGCUGGAUAGCAGGGAUAGGGUAGGAGGGAGGCCACUGGAGGAAAGAGUUAUGAACACUCCAUGGGCACUAACAAAAACAGGAAGAACGCCUGUCAGUGAGAGCCCACAUGUGUCAAGGCCAACGCCACAGUCUCUUGGGCAUAACAGAGGCUGCAGGGGCAAGGGGUGCUGCUUUGCAGGCCCCAGGACACGUCGUCUCAAAGGAGGAGGAGAGGGACCAGCAGGGCCCUGGUGGUUCCCACUCACGUCGUCCCGCACGGCCUGGAUCUGCUGGGGCAGCAGGCCCACUUCUUCCGCCACCGAGCUCUGCUUCAGUGCCAGAGCCGCCAGCUCCUGCUGCAGGCCGGCCAGCUGGUCCUCCAGCCGCCUCAGCUCCUUCACAGAGCUCUCCUGGAAGGACUCCUGGGUCAUGCUGGUCCCAGAGAGAGAAGAGUAAGCCUCGGAUCUCUUUGGUGGGAGGUAAGGCCACACCAAAGAUGAAAGAGGACCCCCUAGUGGGCUCCCGUCAGGAGAGCGGGUGCCCAGCACUCAUUGUGAACCUGAGAAGGGGCAAGGCCUCUCCUGGGGGUUCUGGCUGCAGAACCCCUGCCUGUCCCAAGGAGCUAAUUCUGAGCCUGCUCCCUUUCUAAGCCCAGAGUCCAGAAUGUACUCUGCCUCAGCCUCUCACAUCCUCCACAAGCAUGGACAUCUGGGGCAUGAGAAGGCAGUUAUGUGAGGCUGUAAGAAAGGAUGCUGUGUCUAUAAAUGAAUCCCGGUCCUCUCACACAGCCUGCCCCCCGCCCUCAGGACCCCCCUGCUAACCUCCAUGGCACCUCAAAGACAGGCCCUGGGCAGGGGUCCUGAGCUGGGUUUCAACCCCUCCCCCUACCAUCUGCUUGGCAAGAUGAUCAGAACUCUCUGCUCUGCGGCUCUGCUCCCCAGUCCUGCCUGGAGAGUGGGUGGGGCUGGGGAGGAGCAGGCCGAGGCCAGCUGGUGGCGCCCAGUACCUUUGCCACUCUGACUUCAGCUGCUGGAUGCGAGCCUCGGACUCCUGUGUAGGAAGAAGGGACAAAUACAAGAAAUACUCAUCUCAGAAAUUGGUGUUCCAGAGUAGGAUCUGCUGUCUGUUAGCGUCUUUGCUUAACCACACCCCUGCCCAAGGUCUCUUGACCCCUGCAGCAAAAAUCAAACUGGCCUCCUUGUCAAAGCCCUCAUGAGUCUCGUCCAUGUCUGACACACUGAGGUAUCUGUUCACCCACACUCAGCACAUGCACACCAGCAUGACAGGCCGCUGUGCCCUGGCACACCCCAGGGAGCCCCUGCACAGCUCUCCAACUAAGGGGUCGGGGGUCAAACAGAGAAGUCAGAGGAGGGCACUCCCCUCCCCAUGCAACACCCAAACAGUCCCUUUGGAAGGGCCGAGGGGUCCGAGGUGAACAUGUUGGAUGGGGUCAGGACCCAGUCACAGGCCCUGAGUGCCGCAAGCCCGCUGACCUGGGAGGCCCGGACGAUCUUCUUGAAGAGGUCUUCUGAGUCUUGCUGAUGCUCUGCUCUCAGGGCAGACAGUUCUUCCUGUGAGACGGGAGUGAGAGGACAGGUUGGACAGAGCCAUGCUUAUAGGGACCCUCAUGACUAGGAAGUGGCGGAACUGGAAUUCAAACAAGGUCUGUUUGCUUCCAGAGCCCUGGCUCUCAGCCUUCUCUGAACCACGCAAGACUCCCGCUUCAGCUCCACUGCACACCUCUGCGGUGUCAGGUACCAUGCUGGGGCUUUCUACUCGCACAGCUCACUAUGGGGGUGGGGGAGACACGAUGGCCUCCAUCAAAGAGCAGGAAACUGAGGCUUAGAGAAGGUGAGGAGGCCUGGCGUGGUGGCUCACGCCUGUAAUCCCAGGACUUUGGGAGGCCAAGGCAGGCAGAUCACUAGAGGUCAGGAGUUCGAGACCAGCCUGGCCAACUUGGUAAAACCCUGUCUCUACUAAAAAUACAAAAUUAGCUGGAUGUGGUGGUGCACGCCUGUAAUCCAGCUACUCGGGAGGCUGAGUGAGGCAAGAGAAUCGCUUGAACCUGGGAGGCACAGGUUGUAGUGAGUCGAGAUCACGCCACUGCACUCCAGGCUGGGUGACAGAGUGAGAUAUUGUCUCAAAAAGAAAAAAAAAAAAGAAAAAAAGAGAAAGGGAGUAACUGCAAAAUGGCAGAGCUGUCUGAUCCCAAAUGACACUUGUUCUCUCUGCUGCUGGGCACCUUCACGCUUUCCUAUGGGUGUCACCCACCUCCCACCCUGAGGUAUUCCACCUCCUACCUGGAUGCGAGCAGCAGUUUCCCUGCGGAAAUCCUCCUUCAGGGCAGCUUCACGGCGGCUCACUAGCCCCUCCAGCAGCGCCAGGGUGUCCUCGUGGCUCAGGCCACCACCACCUCCCUGGCCAGGAGCCCCUUGCCGCAGCUCCAGACGUUCCAGCCGCAUGGCCUCCUUCUGCCAGUUGGAGGAAAAUUCAGCAGCAAGAGCUUCCAGACGCCGCUCCAGAGAGUGUACCCGGGACAUAACACGCUGCUCAGCCUGGAAGGGCAGAGAGAGAGCCACGGAGUGAGGGACCCUUGGAUGAUAGUGCUUCCCAAAGACCACCCCGACACAGCCAACACAGAAAGAAAGGGAAAAGAUUCCAGAGACGUUCCAGCAUAAGGCCAUGCAGGGCCGGCUGGAGCUCGUGGGCAGGGGCUGCCGACCUCUGAGCUGGGUGUGCUGGGAGCCAGGGAUCACUGGGUGCCGGCCACAGAGGAAGGUCCCUGAGGACACAGUACCGAAGUCUGAUCCCAGAGGAGGAAGGAAGGUGGGCCGGGGAGAAGGUCUGAGUGCAGGGAUGGUCCAGGAGGAGGACUGGAAGCUGCAGGAUGGCUGCAGGGGGCCGUGGACCCUCCUGGCCUGAAGCUCACUCCUUCCCCGCCUCCUACAGGGGCAGGGGAGCCAGGGCUGCGAGUUCUGUCUGUGGACUCUCAAUGGCUUUCACUCCUUCCCUAGGUAACUAUGGCUAAGAGACAGAAUAAUUUGAAAAUACGUUCUUUUUCCUCUUUAGCUGGAUGUCCCACAGAGAAAAUGGAAUAAAUGUCAUUUGGACUGAG